AGAGGCGGCUUCUGAAAAGCCAAGGUAGUAUCUGCCUGCUGAAGGUGUUCUCAGGAUUUCAUUUGCUCUUCUCCAGGAACCACAUCACCUGCCCUUCUGCCUACACUCCUGCCUGCUGUGCCUAACCACAGCCAUCAUGCCUCGGGGUCAGAAGAGUAAGCUCCGUGCCCGUGAGAAACGCCAGCGGACCCGUGGUCAGACCCAGGAUCUCAAGGUUGGUCAGCCUACUGCAGCAGAGAAAGAAGAGUCUCCUUCCUCUUCCUCAUCUGUUUUGAGGGAUACUGCCUCCAGCUCCCUUGCUUUUGGCAUUCCCCAGGAGCCUCAGAGAGAGCCACCCACCACCUCUGCUGCUGCAGCUAUGUCAUGCACUGGAUCUGAUAAAGGCGACGAGAGCCAAGAUGAGGAAAAUGCAAGUUCCUCCCAGGCCUCAACAUCCACUGAGAGAUCACUCAAAGAUUCUCUAACCAGGAAGACGAAGAUGUUAGUGCAGUUCCUGCUGUACAAGUAUAAAAUGAAAGAGCCCACUACAAAGGCAGAAAUGCUGAAGAUCAUCAGCAAAAAGUACAAGGAGCACUUCCCUGAGAUCUUCAGGAAAGUCUCUCAGCGCACGGAGCUGGUCUUUGGCCUUGCCUUGAAGGAGGUCAACCCCACCACUCACUCCUACAUCCUCGUCAGCAUGCUAGGCCCCAACGAUGGAAACCAGAGCAGUGCCUGGACCCUUCCAAGGAAUGGGCUUCUGAUGCCUCUACUGAGUGUGAUCUUCUUAAAUGGCAACUGUGCCCGUGAAGAGGAAAUCUGGGAAUUCCUGAAUAUGCUGGGGAUCUAUGAUGGAAAGAGGCACCUUAUCUUUGGGGAACCCCGAAAGCUCAUCACCCAAGAUCUGGUACAGGAAAAAUAUCUGGAAUACCAGCAGGUGCCCAACAGUGAUCCCCCACGCUAUCAAUUCCUGUGGGGUCCAAGAGCUCAUGCAGAAACCAGCAAGAUGAAAGUCCUGGAGUUUUUGGCCAAGGUGAAUGACACCACCCCCAAUAACUUCCCACUGCUUUAUGAAGAGGCUUUGAGAGAUGAAGAAGAGAGAGCUGGAGCCCGGCCCAGAGUUGCAGCCAGGCGUGGCACUACAGCCAUGACUAGUGCGUAUUCCAGGGCCACAUCCAGUAGCUCUUCCCAACCCAUGUGAGAUCUAAGGCAAAUUGUUCACUUUGUGGUUGAAAGACCUGCUGCUUUCUCUGUUCCUGUGAUGCAUGAAUAACUCAUUGAUUUAUCUCUUUGUUGUAUUUUCCAUGAUGUUUCUUAAAAUAGAAAGUUUAUUUAGAUUCAGAAUAUAAAUUUAGAAAUGGCAUGCAUCACACAUUUAUUGCUGUUUAUCAGGUUGGUUUAGUGAUAAUAAUUUUGUUUUUGAAAUACAAAUAGAAAAUCCUGAAAUAAUUUUUGUGAUACAGAGCAAAAUAACACGGCAUGGGAGUAAGGUUAUCCUUAGAAAUUUAAAAUAACUCCACAGUAAAAUAGGUAGAAUCUGAAGAUAGAAAGGGAAGAAAAGUAAAAGUUGCUUUAUUCGUGGUUUGUCUUACUCAGUUCAGUCUUUUUUUGCUCAUAAAUUUAAAAGUUACAUACCUGGUUUGCUUAGAUUAUUCAAGAAUGUGGAGGCCUGGGCCAAGGUCAAUGACAGUGUCUCCAUUGUCUUCCCUCCAUUAAGAGAAGACUUUAAGAGAUGAGGGAGAGAGAGCCAGAGACAGUGUUGCAACUGGGCCUGGCAUGUUUCAGUGUGGUGUCCAGCAGUGUCUCCCACUCCUUGUGAAGUCUGAGGUAUAUUCUUUACUUUUGAUUAAGAAAACACUUAACCUUCUAAUUAAUGGAGAGCCAAAGGGGAGUUGGUGGGAACACCAUGUAUAACAUAUUUGUAUGUAAAAUGAUUUAUCUUUUCUUUUUCCUGUUUUUCAGUGUUCUUUUUUUAAAUUGUAGAUUUAUUUAGUUUCAGAAUCUAAGUUUAUGAAUGGCAUGAAUCACUCAUUUAUUAAAAUAUAUCAGGUUGGAGAGUGAGAAUUUUUGCAUUAUGUAAAACAAUUUAAAAAUCUUUUAAGUCUUUUUCUGUGAUCUAGAACAAGAUAAUAUGGCAUUGGAAUAUGGAAUUUGUGAAAAGGAAAUUACCUUGCAAUAAAGUUGGUGGGACCAGGAAGUAGAGAAAAAAAAA